GGACUCAGCCCUGGCCUCGCCGAGCUCUGUUCUUAGACUCUCACCCGUCCCGCACGUUCCUGGGCGCCUGGCGUUCUGAUUCGCCCGCCCGGGCCCCGCCACCCCCUCCUCAGCUGACGGGGCAAAAGCUGCUCCGAGAGGAGAAGGUCAAGUCCUCCGCCCGGGCCGGGCGCGAGCGGAGCCCAGGGAGCGCAGCAUCCGCGCGGCUACCGCGGCGGCGCAGGAGUUAUAAAGUCGGCGCGCGAGACUCCGCCGCCACCCGGCAGCCCCGGCGCAGCUCCGGCAGCCGCAGUCGCAGCGCCCCCAGCGUGGCGCCCCCCGGCCGGGCCUGCCGCCCGGGACCCGGGCUGGGGCGCAGAGGGAGCCCGGAGCCCGGCGCCCCCAUGCGCCGCCCCGCCGCCGCCGCGCCACAGCUAUGACCCUGAGCACUGAGAUGUCCGAUGCCUCUGGCCUCGCCGAGGAAACAGACAUCGACGUGGUGGGGGAGGGCGAGGACGAAGAAGACGAGGAAGAGGAGGACGACGACGAGGGCGGCGGUGGCGGGCCCCGGCUGGCUGUCCCCGCGCAGCGGCGGCGGCGGCGGCGCUCGUACGCCGGGGAGGACGAGCUGGAGGAUCUGGAGGAGGAGGAGGACGACGAUGACAUCCUGCUGGCCCCGCCUGCUGGGGGCUCCCCGGCGCCCCCGGGCCCGGCCCCGGCGGCGGGGGCAGGAGCCGGUGGGGGCGGCGGCGGCGGCGGCGCGGGCGGCGGCGGGAGCGCGGGUAGCGGCGCCAAGAACCCGCUGGUGAAGCCGCCCUACUCGUAUAUCGCGCUCAUCACUAUGGCCAUCCUGCAGAGCCCCAAGAAGCGGCUGACGCUGAGCGAGAUCUGUGAGUUCAUCAGCGGCCGCUUCCCCUACUACCGGGAGAAGUUCCCCGCCUGGCAGAACAGCAUCCGCCACAACCUCUCGCUCAACGACUGCUUCGUCAAGAUCCCCCGCGAGCCCGGCAACCCGGGCAAGGGCAACUACUGGACGCUGGACCCGGAGUCCGCCGACAUGUUCGACAACGGCAGCUUCCUGCGCCGGAGGAAGCGCUUCAAGCGGCAGCCGCUGCUCCCACCCAACGCCGCGGCCGCCGAGUCUCUGCUGCUGCGCGGCGCGGGAGCCGCAGGGGGCGCGGGCGACCCGGCAGCCGCCGCCGCGCUCUUCCCGCCCGCGCCCCCGCCGCCCCCGCAUGCCUACGGCUACGGCCCCUACGGCUGCGGCUACGGCCUGCAGCUGCCGCCUUACGCGCCGCCCUCGGCCCUCUUCGCCGCCGCAGCGGCCGCCGCCGCCGCCGCCGCCUUCCACCCGCACUCGCCCCCGCCGCCCCCGCCACCGCACGGCGCGGCCGCCGAGCUGGCCCGGACCGCCUUCGGCUACCGGCCGCACCCGCUCGGCGCCGCCCUACCCGGCCCCCUGCCGGCCUCCGCGGCCAAGGCGGGCGGCCCGGGCGCCUCAGCGCUGGCGCGCUCGCCCUUCUCCAUCGAGAGCAUCAUCGGGGGCAGCUUGGGCCCGGCCGCCGCUGCCGCCGCCGCCGCGCAGGCCGCCGCCGCCGCUCAGGCCUCGCCCUCGCCCUCGCCGGUGGCGGCGCCGCCAGCUCCCGGAUCCAGCGGAGGAGGCUGCGCGGCGCAGGCGGCCGUGGGCCCGGCGGCCGCGCUCACCCGAUCCCUCGUGGCCGCCGCGGCCGCCGCCGCCUCCUCAGUCUCCUCGUCCGCCGCCUUGGGGACUCUGCACCAAGGGACUGCCCUGUCCAGUGUCGAGAACUUUACUGCUAGGAUUUCCAAUUGUUAAUAACGCUAUGUUAGCGCGCUCGAGGAAGAAGGUAGGAAUCCCGGCUCCUUUUCUCGUCUUGGUGGUUCGGUGUUUUGUUCGCUCCUCCAGGCGCGGCCCCUCUCGACCUCGCGCGCCCAUUUUCGCCGCUGCGAAUUCUCGGACAAAACUGUCAACAGCCCGGGCGCGCCUUUUGGCUCUGCGGGUCCCUCUAUUUAUGCAAAGCCGACCUAUGCUACAGCCCCCCAACCCCCGACCUGGGGUAGGGAGGAAGAGGGUGCCGGGGAAGGGAGUCCGCCCUGUCCAGGCACUAGAGGCUCCCUUGACGUUUGGCAGAUGAAAAACAACUAAGCCUUUUUGAGGUGUAGAGAUUCUCAGGUCCAGGCGUUAAAAAAUAAUGGUCAAAAGAAUAAUACAAAAAUAGUAAAGGUCUUGAAGAAUGCCAGCGAAGCAAUUCUUUUUUAUUUGAGGACACUUGUCUGGUGUACUUUUUCAUGAAAAGGAAAAAUGGUUAACAUGUUUACACAAGAAAAAAAGUCAAAAUUAUCAUUUAUUUCAACCUGUGUUUUGUAUCAUAACAGACGUGUGGAUUUUUUUGUACUUACUGCGUAUUCUUUACAAGGAGUAUUGUAAAUUUUACUGGCAAUUAUUAUUGUACUAUUCUAAAUGUAAGAUUUUUACACUUUUUCAGAAAUAAAAAUGCUUAAUUUUCAAAGAAAA